ACCCAUGGUCCCAAGCGAGGCCUGGCGCGGGACGCCGGACGCGGUGCGGGGCGGAGCGGGGCGCCAAGGGGCGCGCCAGGAGCUGCGCGGGCGCUGGGAGGGAGACCAGGGCGCAGUUCCGGGCGCGUCUGAGCGGUUCUCGAGGCGUUCUCGCCUCGGUCUCUGGCGAGUGCACGGGUUGGUAUCCCAGAGGAGGUUAAAGCUGUUCCUUGAGACCUCCGCUGCUAAAUAGAGUCGCAGUAGUGACCCGAUUCGUCCAGCAACGCGGGGCUGACUUCCCGCCUCCAAGCCCUGAGCUUGGCACCGUGGCGGUGGGGGGUGGGGGUGGGGGGUCUCCGAAAGGGAAUCAGACCCGGCCCCCGUCCUUAGAGAAGAGGACAGUGUGUGGGGGCACUUUAUGCCGUCAGUAACCCCACCUCCAGGUAGACGUGGUACAGGCCCCAAGGGUGUUGGAAUCACAGCUGGGAAAUCAGGGACGCCGUCCCGGAGGAGGUGCCAUUUGAGCCGAGUCGAAGAACGUGUGGGAAUUUUCCAGGUGGACUCCAUAAGCCAGGAUCAAAAGCAGCAUGGAUCUGCCUGUGGAUGAAUGGAAAUCAUAUCUGCUUCAAAAGUGGGCUUCACUCCCGACGUCUGUUCAGGUCACAAUUUCUACAGCAGAGACCUUGAGGGAUAUCUUUCUUCACUCCUCUUCACUUCUUCAACCUGAGGAUGAGCUGUUUCUAAAAAGACUUUCUAAAGGUUACUUGGUGGGAAAGGACUCGGACGCUCCUCUUUUCUACAGAGAAGAAGGAAACAAAAAAUUUCAGGAGAAAGAUUACACAGGAGCUGCAGUGCUGUACUCUAAGGGAGUGUCACAUUCAAGGCCUAACACUGAGGACAUGUCACUGUGUCAUGCUAACCGCUCGGCAGCCCUCUUCCACCUGGGUCAGUAUGAGACGUGUCUUAAAGACAUUAACAGAGCACAGACACAUGGGUAUCCAGAAAGGUUGCAACCCAAGAUUAUGUUACGUAAAGCAGAAUGUCUGGUGGCCCUGGGGAGACUGCAGGAGGCAAGCCAGACCAUCAGUGAUCUUGAAAGGAACUUCACAGCCACACCAGCCCUAGCAGAUGUCCUCCCUCAGACUCUGCAGAGAAACCUCCAUCGUCUGAAAAUGAAGAUGCAAGAAAAGGACAGUCUCACAGAAAGCUUCCCAGCAGCUCUGGCCAAAACCCUUGAGGAUGCAGCGCUGAGGGAGGAGAAUGAACAACUUUCCAAUGCCUCAUCAUCCAUCGGCUUAUGCGUAGAUCCUUUAAAAGGUCGCUGUCUCGUUGCCACAAAAGAUAUUCUCCCAGGAGAGCUCCUGGUGCAGGAGGAUGCUUUUGUGAGUGUUCUCAACCCAGGAGAACUGCCACCACCGCAUCACGGCCUAGACAGCAAAUGGGACACCAGAGUCACCAAUGGGGACCUCUAUUGUCACCGAUGUUUGAAGCACACUUUGGCCACAGUUCCGUGUGACGGAUGCAGUUAUGCCAAGUAUUGCAGCCAGGAGUGUUUGCAGCAGGCCUGGGAGCUCUACCACAGGACAGAAUGUCCUCUGGGAGGGCUGCUUCUCACACUGGGUGUCUUUUGCCACAUUGCCCUGAGGUUGACUCUUUUGGUGGGAUUUGAGGAUGUUCGCAAAAUCAUAACGAAGCUUUGUGAUAAGAUUAGUAACAAGGACAUCUGUUUACCUGAAAGCAACAAUCAGGUCAAGACACUUAAUUAUGGCCUAGGGGAGAGUGAGAAAAAUGGCAACAUCGUUGAGACCCCAAUUCCUGGAUGCGAUAUUAAUGGGAAGUAUGAAAAUAAUUAUAAUGCUGUCUUCAACCUUUUGCCCCACACUGAAAACCAUAGCCCAGAGCACAAAUUCCUCUGUGCUCUCUGUGUUUCUGCACUGUGCAGACAGCUAGAAGCAGCCAGUUUACAGGCCAUCCCAACUGAGAGGAUUGUGAACUCCUCUCAGCUUAAAGCAGCAGUGACACCUGAAUUGUGUCCUGACGUGACUAUUUGGGGAGUGGCGAUGCUGAGACACAUGUUACAGCUUCAGUGUAACGCUCAGGCGAUGACCACCAUACAACACACAGGACCUAAAGGGAGCAUCGUUACCGACAGCAGGCAGGUGCGCCUUGCCACAGGCAUCUUCCCUGUUAUCAGCCUCCUGAACCACUCCUGUAGCCCCAACACCAGCGUGUCCUUCAUUAGCACUGUCGCCACCAUCCGGGCGUCACAGCGGAUUAGAAAGGGGCAAGAGAUUCUCCACUGCUAUGGGCCUCACAAGAGCCGGAUGGGGGUUGCCGAAAGGCAGCAGAAGCUGAGGUCUCAGUAUUUCUUUGACUGCGCCUGUCCAGCUUGUCAAACUGAGGCACACAGGAUGGCUGCAGGGCCCAGGUGGGAAGCAUUCUGUUGCAACAGUUGCGGAGCGCCCAUGCAGGGAGAUGACGUGCUGCGCUGUGGCAGCAGAUCUUGUGCAGAAUCCGCCGUCAGCAGGGACCACCUGGUCUCUCGGUUACAGGACCUACAGCAGCAGGUCAGAGUGGCCCAGAAGCUUCUCAGAGAUGGUGAACUAGAGCGAGCUGUUCAGCGGCUGUCGGGGUGCCAGCGUGACGCCGAGAGCUUCCUGUGGGCAGAGCACGCCGUGGUGGGAGAGAUCGCGGAUGGCCUGGCCCGGGCCUGUGCUGCCUUAGGAGACUGGCAAAAGUCAGCCACCCAUCUACAGAGGAGUCUCUACGUGGUGGAGGUUCGCCACGGGCCGUCCAGUGUUGAAAUGGGCCAUGAGCUCUUCAAAUUGGCCCAGAUCUUUUUCAACGGGUUUGCAGUACCCGAAGCCCUGAGCACAAUACAGAAAGCUGAGGAGGUUCUGUCGCUGCACUGUGGCCCAUGGGACGAUGAAAUCCAGGAGCUCCAGAAGAUGAAAUCCUGUUUGUUGGACUUACCACCCACCCCUGUAGGGCCUGCAUUGUAGGGUUCCAGGAGGAUUUUGACCCACAGAAAAGGAGCCCAUGGAACACAAGUUAAAGAGGUUUUGCUGGCCAGGUAUGGUGGCUCACGCCUGUAAUCCCAGCACUUUGGGAGGCUAAGGUGGGCGGAUCACCUGAUGUCAGGAGUUCAAGACCAGCCUGGCCAACAUGGUGAAACCCCAUCUUUACUAAAAAUACAAAAAACUAGCCAGGCGUGGUGGUGGGCACCUGUAAUCCCAGCUACUUGGGAGGCUGAGGCAGGAGAAUCUCUUGAACCCAGGAGGCGGAGGUUGCAGUGAGCCGAGAUCGCUCCACUGCACUCCAGCCCAGGUGACAGUGUGAGACUCCAUCUCAAAAAAAAAAAUAAGAGGCCGGGUGCGGUGGCUCAAGCCUGUAAUCCCAGCACUUUGGGAGGCCGAGGCAGGCAGAUCACGAGGUCAGGAGAUCCAGACCAUCCUGGCUAACACGGUGAAACCCCGUCUCUACUAAAAAUACAAAAAAAUUAGUCGGGCGUGGUGGCGGACGCCUGUAUUCACAGCUACUCGGGAGGUUGAGGCAGGAGAAUGGGGUGAACCCGGGAGGAAGAGCUUGCAGUGAGCCGAGAUCGCGCCACUGCACUCCAGCCUGGGUGACAGAGCCAGACUCCAUCUCAAAGAAAAAAAAAAAAUAUUAAGAGGUUCUGCUGCCAGAUGUGGGUUCUGUGGGUCGGGUGUGGGUUCUGUGGGUCGGGUGUGGGUUCUGCAGACCAGGUGCGGAUUCUGUGUAGGUUCUGCAGGCCCAGUGUAGAGGCUCACACCUGUAAUCCCAGUACUUUGAGACGCUGAGGUGGGAGGAUCACUUGAGCCCAGGAGUUCAAAACCAGCCUGGGCAAUAUAGUGAGACCGUAUCACUACAAAAAAGUUUUUUUAGUUCACCGAGCAUGGUGGCACAUGCCUGUAGUCCCACCUACUCGAGAAGCUGAGAUAGGGUCACCUGAGCCUGGUAGGCUGAGGCUGCAGUGAGCCAAGAUCGCACUACUGCACUCCAGCCUGGGUGACAGAGUAAGACCCUGUCUCAACAAAAAAAUAACAGGUUCUGUUGCUGCUGAGCUUUCGUCAGGAAGAUAAGACUUUCCCAACAGUCCGAAGCCUAGGAUAUGAGGGCUGAGGAGGACUCAAACCGUUGCAGUCAGAGAGACACCUAUUUUGGUGAAUAUUUUUUGAAAUAGUUAAGUGGCCUCCAGUACAAACUCCCAGUUCCCAGAAAAGACUUAAAACUAGUAUCUGGAGAUUCCAAGUCCUUUAAAAGGAUUUUAGCUGAUCUGCAGGCAUCUGGAUGUUAGCCUGGGGUUUUGGCUGGAUUCCACCUCGCUCAGUGAUGAUAGUCUGUUUCCCUGGAACAUUCCUGUGGUUUUAGUAGUAAUGAGAUGUGUGCACCACUCCAGUGGGAACUGAAGCUCUUAGUAGUUACAUUGUAAUUAAAAAAGAAUUAUAAAACAAGAAAUCAGCAAGCCUGCUUACCUCCAGAGACACACCGUUCCACUUACAGUAUCUAGCUUCCUCGACUCCUUUGUUAAAAUCGUGGAGUAUGAACCGUGACCAGAGAAGUAAAUAUGGAGCCGUUUUAUUGAGCAGUUUCCUCCAGGGAUGACGGCUGUCAGUGUGUUUCCUGCCAGUUUUCCAGUCCUUACUCUCUGCCCUUCAUUCUGUACUCUUGGCAGAGUCAGUAACCAACCACUAAUAAAAUCAAAGUUGUAGUAAAGACUUUAUAACACAUAUGCCUCCUUCUGAGUUGUUGGUUUUGUUUUGUUUUGUUUUGUUUUGUUUU